ACAGCUCGUCCGCCCUCGCUGCAGCCGGGAGGAGGCGGCGGCCCGUGCACCGCAGGCCCCGCCCGCCCACGGCCCUUCCCGGGAGGCCGGGAGACCUGCUCCGCCCGGCCCUCGGUGGGUGAGUGCGAGCGGCGGGUGGGGCCUCCGCGGGCGGAGGCACCGGGAGCGGGGGCGACGCCUGUCAUCGCUCUAGGCCCAGCGGGAGGACGCGCCAACAUCCCCGCUGCUGUGCUGGGCCCGGGGCGUGCCCGCCGCUGCUCCCACCUCUGGGCCGGGCUGGGGCCGCCCGGGGGCCCUGUUCCUCGGCAUUGCGGGCCUGGUGGGCAGAGCCGCGGAGAGGGCUUCUUUUCCCCAAGGGCAGCGUCUUGGGGCCCGGCCACUGGCUGACCCGCAGCGGCUCCGGCCAUGCCUGGCUGGCCCUGGGGGCUGCUGCUGACGGCAGGCACGCUCUUCGCCGCCCUGAGUCCUGGGCCGCCGGCGCCCGCCGACCCCUGCCACGAUGAGGGGGGUGCGCCCCGCGGCUGCGUGCCAGGACUGGUGAACGCCGCCCUGGGCCGCGAGGUGCUGGCUUCCAGCACGUGCGGGCGGCCGGCCACUCGGGCCUGCGACGCCUCCGACCCGCGACGGGCACACUCCCCCGCCCUCCUUACUUCCCCAGGGGGCACGGCCAGCCCUCUGUGCUGGCGCUCGGAGUCCCUGCCUCGGGCGCCCCUCAACGUGACUCUCACGGUGCCCCUGGGCAAGGCUUUUGAGCUGGUCUUCGUGAGCCUGCGCUUCUGCUCAGCUCCCCCAGCCUCCGUGGCCCUGCUCAAGUCUCAGGACCAUGGCCGCAGCUGGGCCCCGCUGGGCUUCUUCUCCUCCCACUGUGACCUGGACUAUGGCCGUCUGCCUGCCCCUGCCAAUGGCCCAGCUGGCCCAGGGCCUGAGGCCCUGUGCUUCCCCGCACCCCUGGCCCAGCCUGAUGGCAGCGGCCUUCUGGCCUUCAGCAUGCAGGACAGCAGCCCCCCAGGCCUGGACCUGGACAGCAGCCCAGUGCUCCAAGACUGGGUGACCGCCACCGACGUCCGUGUAGUGCUCACAAGGCCUAGCACGGCAGGUGACCCCAGGGACAUGGAGGCCGUCGUCCCUUACUCCUACGCAGCCACCGACCUCCAGGUGGGCGGGCGCUGCAAGUGCAAUGGACAUGCCUCACGGUGCCUGCUGGACACACAGGGCCACCUGAUCUGCGACUGUCGGCAUGGCACCGAGGGCCCUGACUGCGGCCGCUGCAAGCCCUUCUACUGCGACAGGCCAUGGCAGCGGGCCACUGCCCGGGAAUCCCACGCCUGCCUCGCUUGCUCCUGCAACGGCCAUGCCCGCCGCUGCCGCUUCAACAUGGAGCUGUACCGACUGUCCGGCCGCCGCAGCGGGGGUGUCUGUCUCAACUGCCGGCACAACACCGCCGGCCGCCACUGCCACUACUGCCGGGAGGGCUUCUAUCGAGACCCUGGCCGUGCCCUGAGUGACCGUCGGGCUUGCAGGGCCUGCGACUGUCACCCGGUUGGUGCUGCUGGCAAGACCUGCAACCAGACCACAGGCCAGUGUCCCUGCAAGGAUGGCGUCACUGGCCUCACCUGCAACCGCUGCGCGCCUGGCUUCCAGCAAAGCCGCUCCCCAGUGGCGCCCUGUGUUAAGACCCCUAUCCCUGGACCCACUGAGGACAGCAGCCCUGUGCAGCCCCAGGACUGUGACUCGCACUGCAAACCUGCCCGUGGCAGCUACCGCAUCAGCCUAAAGAAGUUCUGCAAGAAGGACUAUGCGGUGCAGGUGGCGGUGGGUGCGCGCGGCGAGGCGCGCGGCGCGUGGACACGCUUCCCGGUGGCGGUGCUCGCCGUGUUCCGGAGCGGAGAGGAGCGCGCGCGGCGCGGGAGUAGCGCGCUGUGGGUGCCCGCCGGGGAUGCGGCCUGCGGCUGCCCGCGCCUGCUCCCCGGCCGCCGCUACCUCCUGCUGGGGGGCGGGCCUGGAGCCGCGGCUGGGGGCGCGGGGGGCCGGGGGCCCGGGCUCAUCGCCGCCCGCGGAAGCCUCGUGCUACCCUGGAGGGACGCGUGGACGCGGCGCCUGCGGAGGCUGCAGCGACGCGAACGGCGGGGGCGCUGCAGCGCCGCCUGAGCCCGCCGGCUGGGCAGGGCGGCCGCUGCUCCCACAUCUA